UUGCAUUCUUUAAACAGCUAUUGAGCACACUAUGGCAAACCUAAAAUAGCUGUUCAGUGCCUUUGUCACUUGAGCAGCAGUCACUUGAUGCUGUUCUUCAAUCCUGCCAUUUUCUAUCAACAAAGGCAUUUUAAUUUGUUUUGAUUAAUCUAGUAAAAUCCCUUUAACACAUUUGUUUCCUUAGCAAAGGUGUUUUGUUUAUUUCAGUCAGGCGCUGACAGUUGAGAUUAAAGAUCUCCAAAAACAAGCAUCCUUUCUGAACGUGGGACUUAGGGUCUUUCCUGUUUGCAGGUUUUAAUUGAGGUUACCAAGUGCGACAGAACUCACACAAGUGUGUGGGCCUCUGUUGUGUCAGAAAGAGCCACUUAGAGCACAUAAUCUCACCCGAGUGCGUUCCUUAAACUUUGUUUAAAUAUAACAUGUAACUAUAUUAUUUACCAUGUGUUCACAGUUCCCCUCAGUAAUUCUUGUAAUUUUGGGGGUUCUGCCUUCAGUAGCUAUAUUUUCCUCUCACACUUAGCUUUAGCACAAUGUCAGAAAUAAGCAAGAGACUUUGUUACUGACAAAUCUGAUUUUUAAGAUGCUAAAAACUGACAAAACGAUUUUUUUUCUAACAGUGAUAAAUGGAGCCAAGUAGAGUUAAAGGGUAAACUUCCAAAUCUAAAUUGAUGUGUCUUUUAUUUUUUCUUUUGGCAACUAACUACAGAGAAAAGUUUCUUUAUAUACUUUAUUUGUCUAAUUUCCUCAUUUUAAAAAAAAUUUAUCAAUAUGAACACUUGCUAGUUUAAAAUUUUUUAAUUUUUAUUUUAAACAUUUGCUCCUUCCUGCACGAUAAAAUGUAUUUAAAAGCAUAGAAUCACUUUUAAAAUGAAUCUUCUUAUUAAUGACUAGUCAGUUGUGGCUGCAUGGAUGUGUGUGUGUGUGUGUUUGUGUUUUUAAAGUUUCCCUAGCGAUCUAGUGUUUUUUUGUGUGUCAAAGUAUCUUUAGGGUAAGUGCUAGUCCUUUUUAAAAGAGGUAUCAUUAUUUCUUAAUUUUAUAUUUAAUUGGCUUUGUAUAUGUGAUUAGUUAAUGUCAAAGCUAAUGGUGAUAGAAAUUUAUACUCAAUAUAGUAUGGGAGGGGAUACUUUAUUUUAAAGAAAUGAAAGCAUUACAAGAUUUGAAGGAUAGCAUUGUUUGUCAAGAAGGUAUAGUAGGCCUUCACUAUGUAUGAUAAUUAUAUGCCAAUCAUGUGCCUUGGAGAUGCUGACUCAAUUAAGACACUGGUUUUCCUUUCCGUGGAGAAAUCUGGUGGAAAACAGACAGGGAAAUCAACAUAUUACUUUGAAGAUGAGAAUGGAAACUGUAAAACUCUGUAUAGUAGAGAACAGUAGUGCAGAUGGCAGUUUGGUUAACUCUUGGAGAUCAGGGAAAUCUUCCUGGAGGGCAUGGUUAUAUGGAAAUUUAUGAACCAGAAAAUGAAAGCACAAGAGAGAAUAUUUGGAGAGAGAGAAAUAGCAGUCAUGUUAUUGGGAGACUAUACUAUGGUCUGACAUUCCAGGCACAUGUUAUGAUAAACCUGCCUUAAUUAAGAUCACAAAUGUAUACAAAGGCAAAUAGAAAACUUUCAUUAUCUAGAUAAGGUUUUUUCUUUGGACAAGGUAUUGCUCUGCUGCCCUGGCUGGAAUGCAGUGGUGCAAUCCUAGCUCACUGCAGCCUCGAACUCCUGGGCUCAAGUGAUCCUCCUGCCUCAGCCAUCUGAGUAGCUGAUACUAUAGCUGUGCACUAGCAUACCUGGCUAAUUUUUAAAUUUUUAGUAGAGACGGGGGUCUCACUAUAUUGUUCAGGCUGGAAGAUACCUUUUUACAAGUUUUAUUCUAUAAAAAGUCAAACAUCUCCCAAAUCCUUGAGCUGCCUGUUAGGUAUUUUAUUUCAUAGAACGACAUUUAUUGGUGGGGAAACAAUGGUAAUUUGGGGAGAAAAAAGAUCAUGUCAUCUUAAUGUUUGUAAUAAAAAAAGACCCAAACACAGGGCACAUCAAUCUACCUUACUCUUUAAGAAAGCAGAUUUUAUUUAUUUAUUUAUUUAUUUAUUUAUUUAUUUAUUUAUUUAUUCUUUUUUGAGCUAGGGUCUUGGCUCUGUUGACCAGGUGAAGUGCAGUAACGGGAUCACAGCUCAGUGCACCCCCAGCUUCCUGGGCUCAAGUAAUCCUCCUGCCUUAGCUUCCUGAGUAGCUGGGACUGUAGGUAUACACCACCAUGCCAGGCUAAUUUUUAAAUUUUUAUAGCGAUUAGGUCUCAUUAUGUUGCCCAGGCUGGUUGUGAACUCCUGGGCUGUAGCAAUCCUCCUGCCUUGGCCUCCCAAAGUGUUGGGAUUAUAGGCAUGAGCUACUGCACCCAGCAGGAAGCAGUAUUAGAGAGAUCCGUUUCUUGGUCCUGGACUUCAUGUGAAUGUACCUCAAGGGAUGAACAAACAGAAUACCACUUCUGAUAAUGUUAUUUUAAAAACAAAAUAUUUUAGGUUGGUGAAAAAGUAAUUGUGGCUUUUGUCAUUGAAAGUAAUGGCAAAAACCGCAAUUACUUUUGCACCAACCUAUAAUUAUAUAUUGUAACACAUAUUAUGUAAUAUAUAACAAUAGAAUUUGAAAUGUUAUUAUUGAUACUAUUAAGUAAUAUUAUUAUAAAAGAUCCAGAUGUGGAAGAAAAUAGUGUAUUACCUAAAGAAAUUAUUGAGACUGCACAGGGAUAGAACUGUCUCAUGAGCUCUGAUUUUUAAAAAUGUCUGUGUAAAAAAGAUGAAAGGGGCUUAGUCAAGAAAACCUGGGCUUUGGAUGUAUUUAGACCUAGGUUUGAAUCAGAUCUCUGUCACCUAUUUGCCCUUUUACUUAGAGCAAAUUACUAGAUGAUUCUGGUGCACAGGUUCCAGGUCUGUAUAAGGUAAGAUCUAGAAUAUUUGUAUUAUAGUUGUGAAGAUUAAAUGAGAUCGCAUAUAUAGAGCUCUAGCACAGUGCUUCCUUACGCCUUCAUGUGAGAGAGAGAUCAACUUCUGCCGUCAAGGUGUGAGGAGCUCUGCUGACCUGCCUUGCUUGCUGAAACAAGUGAAAACUAUUAAAGAAAACAAAACCCAGUCAUUUAAAGUCUCUGGAAAUCGUCCUAAGAGUAAGCAGAAAAUGAAGGAACAUUAUUCAAGAACAUCUGUGCAAAUUCGCAUCUGAAUAGCAGCUUUCUUCCCAGGAGGAUUUGGACAUCAGCAAUUCUCAUUCUGCCCCGAGCUGCCUAUUGCUGAGUCCUGGAGAAGUGCAGUUAAGAGAUGGGGGCCCCUUCUUCUACUCAGCCCCCACUUGUGGAACUUGAUCAGGAACUGACUUCAUUUGCAACAGGGAGUGAAGAAGUUCAAACCUGAUUGUACUCUCAAGAACAGUAGAGGGAAAAGAAAAAAGAAAAAGAACAGUGGAGGUUGUGGUAAAGGACAUUUGAGAAGAGAUUCAUGAAACAGGCCAAAUGACCACCUGGUGGCCCAUGGUAGAAUGGCAGAAAAGGAGGCACGUCGGAAGUUCAAACAGAUCGUCACAGCUGUCUAUUUUUGUCACUGUCGGAACAUUGUUCAUCGUGAUUUAAAAGCUGAAAAUUUACUUCUGGAUGCCAAUCUGAAUAUCAAAAUAGCAGAUUUUGGUUUCAGUAACCUCUUCACUCCUGGGCAGCUGCUGAAGACCUGGUGUGGCAGCCCUCCCUAUGCUGCACCUGAACUCUUUGAAGGAAAAGAAUAUGAUGGGCCCAAAGUGGACAUCUGGAGCCUUGGAGUUGUCCUCUACGUGCUUGUGUGCGGUGCCCUGCCAUUUGAUGGAAGCACACUGCAGAAUCUGCGGGCCCGCGUGCUGAGUGGAAAGUUCCGCAUCCCAUUUUUUAUGUCCACAGAAUGUGAGCAUUUGAUCCGCCAUAUGUUGGUGUUAGAUCCCAAUAAGCGCCUCUCCAUGGAGCAGAUCUGCAAGCACAAGUGGAUGAAGCUAGGGGACGCCGAUCCCAACUUUGACAGGUUAAUAGCUGAAUGCCAACAACUAAAGGAAGAAAGACAGGUGGACCCCCUGAAUGAGGAUGUCCUCUUGGCCAUGGAGGACAUGGGACUGGACAAAGAACAGACACUGCAGUCAUUAAGAUCAGAUGCCUAUGAUCACUAUAGUGCAAUCUACAGCCUGCUGUGUGAUCGACAUAAGAGACAUAAAACCCUGCGUCUCGGAGCACUUCCUAGCAUGCCCCGAGCCCUGGCCUUUCAAGCACCAGUCAAUAUCCAGGCGGAGCAGGCAGGUACUGCUAUGAACAUCAGCGUUCCCCAGGUGCAGCUGAUCAACCCAGAGAACCAAAUUGUGGAGCCGGAUGGGACACUGAAUUUGGACAGUGAUGAGGGUGAAGAGCCUUCCCCUGAAGCAUUGGUGCGCUAUUUGUCAAUGAGGAGGCACACAGUGGGUGUGGCUGACCCACGCACGGAAGUUAUGGAAGAUCUGCAGAAGCUCCUACCUGGCUUUCCUGGAGUCAACCCCCAGGCUCCAUUCCUGCAGGUGGCCCCUAAUGUGAACUUCAUGCACAACCUGUUGCCUAUGCAAAACUUGCAACCAACCGGGCAACUUGAGUACAAGGAGCAGUCUCUCCUACAGCCGCCCACGCUACAGCUGUUGAAUGGAAUGGGCCCCCUUGGCCGGAGGGCAUCAGAUGGAGGAGCCAACAUCCAACUGCAUGCCCAGCAGCUGCUGAAGCGCCCACGGGGACCCUCUCCGCUUGUCACCAUGACACCAGCAGUGCCAGCAGUUACCCCUGUGGACGAGGAGAGCUCAGACGGGGAGCCAGACCAGGAAGCUGUGCAGAGGUACUUGGCAAAUAGGUCCAAAAGACAUACACUGGCCAUGACCAACCCUACAGCUGAGAUCCCACCGGACCUACAACGGCAGCUAGGACAGCAGCCUUUCCGUUCCCGGGUCUGGCCUCCUCACCUGGUACCUGAUCAGCAUCGCUCUACCUACAAGGACUCCAACACUCUGCACCUCCCUACGGAGCGUUUCUCCCCUGUGCGCCGGUUCUCAGAUGGGGCUGCGAGCAUCCAGGCCUUCAAAGCUCACCUGGAAAAAAUGGGCAACAACAGCAGCAUCAAACAGCUGCAGCAGGAGUGUGAGCAGCUGCAGAAGAUGUACGGGGGGCAGAUUGAUGAAAGAACCCUGGAGAAGACCCAGCAGCAGCAUAUGUUAUACCAGCAGGAGCAGCACCAUCAAAUUCUCCAGCAACAAAUUCAAGACUCUAUCUGUCCUCCUCAGCCAUCUCCACCUCUUCAGGCUGCAUGUGAAAAUCAGCCAGCCCUCCUUACCCAUCAGCUCCAGAGGUUAAGGAUUCAGCCUUCAAGCCCACCCCCCAACCACCCCAACAACCAUCUCUUCAGGCAGCCCAGUAAUAGUCCUCCCCCCAUGAGCAGUGCCAUGAUCCAGCCUCACGGGGCUGCAUCUUCUUCCCAGUUUCAAGGCUUACCUUCCCGCAGUGCAAUCUUUCAGCAGCAACCUGAGAACUGUUCCUCUCCUCCCAACGUGGCACUAACCUGCUUGGGUAUGCAGCAGCCUGCUCAGUCACAGCAGGUCACCAUCCAAGUCCAAGAGCCUGUUGACAUGCUCAGCAACAUGCCAGGCACAGCUGCAGGCUCCAGUGGGCGCGGCAUCUCCAUCAGCCCCAGUGCUGGUCAGAUGCAGAUGCAGCACCGUACCAACCUGAUGGCCACCCUCAGCUAUGGGCACCGUCCCUUGUCCAAGCAGCUGAGUGCUGACAGUGCAGAGGCUCACAGCUUGAACGUGAAUCGGUUCUCCCCUGCUAACUACGACCAGGCGCAUUUACACCCCCAUCUGUUUUCGGACCAGUCCCGGGGUUCCCCCAGCAGCUACAGCCCUUCAACAGGAGUGGGGUUCUCUCCAACCCAAGCCCUGAAAGUCCCUCCACUUGACCAAUUCCCCACCUUCCCUCCCAGUGCACAUCAGCAGCCGCCACACUAUACCACGUCGGCACUACAGCAGGCCCUGCUGUCUCCCACGCCGCCAGACUAUACAAGACACCAGCAGGUACCCCACAUCCUUCAAGGACUGCUUUCUCCCCGGCAUUCGCUCACCGGCCACUCGGACAUCCGGCUGCCCCCAACAGAGUUUGCACAGCUCAUUAAAAGGCAGCAGCAACAACGGCAGCAGCAGCAGCAACAGCAGCAACAGCAAGAAUACCAGGAACUGUUCAGGCACAUGAACCAAGGGGAUGCGGGGAGUCUGGCUCCCAGCCUUGGGGGACAGAGCAUGACAGAGCGCCAGGCUUUAUCUUAUCAAAAUGCUGACUCUUAUCACCAUCACACCAGCCCCCAGCAUCUGCUACAAAUCAGGGCACAAGAAUGUGUCUCACAGGCUUCCUCACCCACCCCGCCCCACGGGUAUGCUCACCAGCCGGCACUGAUGCAUUCAGAGAGCAUGGAGGAGGACUGCUCGUGUGAGGGGGCCAAGGAUGGCUUCCAAGACAGUAAGAGUUCAAGUACAUUGACCAAAGGUUGCCAUGACAGCCCUCUGCUCUUGAGUACCGGUGGACCUGGGGACCCUGAAUCUUUGCUAGGAACUGUGAGUCAUGCCCAAGAAUUGGGGAUACAUCCCUAUGGUCAUCAGCCAACUGCUGCAUUCAGUAAAAAUAAGGUGCCCAGCAGAGAGCCUGUCAUAGGGAACUGCAUGGAUAGAAGUUCUCCAGGACAAGCAGUGGAGCUGCCGGAUCACAAUGGGCUCGGGUACCCAGCACGCCCCUCCGUCCAUGAGCACCACAGGCCCCGGGCCCUCCAGAGACACCACACGAUCCAGAACAGCGACGAUGCUUAUGUACAGCUGGAUAACUUGCCAGGAAUGAGUCUCGUGGCUGGGAAAGCACUUAGCUCUGCCCGGAUGUCGGAUGCAGUUCUCAGUCAGUCUUCGCUCAUGGGCAGCCAGCAGUUUCAGGAUGGGGAAAAUGAGGAAUGUGGGGCAAGCCUGGGAGGUCAUGAGCACCCAGACCUGAGUGAUGGCAGCCAGCAUUUAAACUCCUCUUGCUAUCCAUCUACGUGUAUUACAGACAUUCUGCUCAGCUACAAGCACCCCGAAGUCUCCUUCAGCAUGGAGCAGGCAGGCGUGUAACAAGAAACAGAGAGUUUUGUGUACAGCUUGGGAAUGAAAAGGUUGAUUGUAAACCCACAGUAUCUAGCAGCGUUGUGCCAAAUUGCCCUUGUGUUUCUCUCCACCCAAAAUAUCACAGCUGCUUUCCUCACAUUUGGUUCAUCCGUGUGCUGUUCUUUUGGGUUCUGAGAGGGUUUUGCCAUGUUUGCUUGUAUGACCAAGUCACCAAGGAAAUAAACAGGAAGGAAAUCCAUGUUCUCCAUCUUUUGUGAAAGUAUAUUUGAGUUGGUGGUUUUUUGUUUUGUUUGGGGGUUUGUGUUUUGUUUUGUUUUUGGUAUGUUUUCUUCCAGAGGUGAUAUACUUUCUUUUUUUUCUUCCUUUCUUUUUUUUCUUUCGUUCCUUUUUUGAAACAGGAGAGCAAAGCAGUUAGAGUUCAGAGGCCAGCGGCCUCAGGGCCACUCCCUCCCUAGCCUUCAUCAGCAGAGCACCCUCCAUCCCCCUGCAUUGCUCUUCUGUGAAAGCAAAUACUAAAGGAUGCCAUCCUCUGGAAUCCUAAUGGCAGGCAAAGGGAGAGAGGAAGGGUGACGGCUUCUGGCACUUAGAAAACAAAAAGAACAAAAAAAGAGAAACCCCCAAGCCUGGAACGCAGAGAGGUCUUUACUGCUGGGAUCCACGGAAAACAUGUCUGUCCUAGCCAAGAUCAUAUGAAGAGUUUGGCACGGAGGCUGAGAAUGACCUGGCAUAGAUGGUUUGCCAGUUAGGAUGUCUCAAUUUGAGCCUUUGCUUUUGGUGGAUAACUCAGCUCCCCUCUUGUAACCUGGAAAGUUGGUUGCCUUUAUCAUCCUGCUGGUUUUAUCCAUGGACUGAACACCCAACAGCAGUGCACUAUGCUUUCUAUGGCAUCUUUCAUUCUCAUUUUAUAUUGUGCUAUAAAAAGGAUUGUUUCUCCAUAUAUAUAUUAUAUAUGUGUGUAUAUAUAUAAUAUAAUAUAUGUGUAUAUAUAUAUUAUAUAUAUAAUAUAUAAUAUAAUAUAUUAUAUAUAUAUUAUAUAUAUAAUAUAUAUAUAAAAUAUAUAUAUAUAUGCUCUCCUCUUUCAGCCUCUUUGUCACAGGGAAGAAGUGUAGGAGGUUGCCUUGGGCCCUGCCUCUCUCCUAACCUCCUCUUCCCCACUGGGUACCCUCAGCCCCUAUAUUUUAAUUCUUGAUCAUGUAGAAAUUGUUUUUGGUAAAUGUUGAUAUUAUUGUUAUUAUCAUUAUUAAUAAAUAAAGAGAAAAGGAAUUUUUGUUUAAAUGAGAAAUGUUUAACCAGAUUCUGUUCUAUUUGAAUUGUGACUUGCACCUUUUGUUCAAAGUAUUUCCUUUAGGCAUUGUAAUUGUGAACAGCUCUUACUUGUGCCAGUGACAGAUGCAGUGGUCUCCUUUCCCCAGUUGAAGCAGUGCAUACGCAGUAGCUAUUAUUUGUGUUAUCUUUAUUUCUCUUCAUUGUUAGAAACCAAAGUCUUCUCUGCUGGCUGGGGCUGAGAGAGGGUCUGGGUUAUCUCCUUCUGAUCUUCAAAACAAGAGAGAGACCUUGAAUACACUGACUCUUCCACCCUUUUUUUUUCUGGGAAAGGAGAGCAAGAGGUCCCGAGUCCCCUCCUAGUCUUUCAUCCUGAAUUUGCACAGAGGAAAGCGGGUGCCCGGCAUGGCCAUCCUGAUGUUGCUGGCGGGAUCCCCAUGCACCUUGUCCUUCUCCACUGAUACUGGCAGCUCGGCUCCUGGACCCAAGAUCCCUUGAGUGGAAUUCUGCAGUGCAAGAGCCCUUCGUGGGAGCUGUCCCAUGUUUCCAUGGUCCCCAGUCUCCCCUCCACUUGGUGGGGUCACCAACUACUCACCAGAAGGGGGCUUACCAAGAAAGCCCUAAAAAGCUGUUGACUUAUCUGCGCUUGUUCCAACUCUUAUGCCCCCAACCUGCCCUACCACCACCACGCGCUCAGCCUGAUGUGUUUACAUGGUACUGUAUGUAUGGGAGAGCAGACUGCACCCUCCAGCAACAACAGAUGAAAGCCAGUGAGCCUACUAACCGUGCCAUCUUGCAAACUACACUUUAAAAAAAACUCAUUGCUUUGUAUUGUAGUAACCAAUAUGUGCAGUAUACGUUGAAUGUAUAUGAACAUACUUUCCUAUUUCUGUUCUUUGAAAAUGUCAGAAAUAUUUUUUUCUUUCUCAUUUUAUGUUGAACUAAAAAGGAUUAAAAAAAAAAUCUCCAGACUCAAGUUGCUAA